AUUGUGGGAAAAGAUGGCGGCUGCCGCACAAUCCCGGGUUGUCCGGGUCCUGUCAAUGUCACGUUCUGCCAUUACUGCAAUAGCCACAUCUGUGUGUCACGGCCCACCCUGUCGCCAGCUUCAUCAUGCCCUCAUGCCUCAUGGGAAAGGUGGACGUUCCUCAGUCAGUGGGAUUGUGGCCACUGUGUUUGGAGCAACAGGAUUCCUGGGGCGAUAUGUUGUCAACCACCUUGGACGCAUGGGGUCACAGGUAAUCAUACCCUAUCGGUGUGAUAAAUAUGACAUCAUGCACCUUCGUCCCAUGGGUGACCUGGGCCAGCUUCUGUUUCUGGAAUGGGACGCGAGAGAUAAAGAUUCUAUCCGACGAGUAGUACAACACAGCAAUGUGGUCAUCAAUCUUAUUGGACGAGACUGGGAAACCAAAAACUUUGAUUUUGAGGAUGUUUUUGUGAAGAUUCCCCAAGCAAUUGCUCAACUGUCCAAGGAAGCUGGAGUUGAAAAAUUCAUUCAUGUUUCACAUCUGAAUGCGAAUAUUAAAAGCUCUUCUAGAUAUUUGAGAAAUAAGGCUGUUGGAGAGAAAGUAGUGAGAGAUGCAUUUCCGGAAGCCAUUAUCGUAAAGCCGUCGGACAUCUUUGGAAGAGAGGAUAGAUUCCUUAAUUCUUUUGCAAGUAUGCAUCGGUUUGGUCCUAUACCCCUUGGUUCCUUGGGCUGGAAGACAGUUAAACAACCAGUAUAUGUCGUAGAUGUAUCCAAAGGAAUUGUUAAUGCAGUUAAGGAUCCUGAUGCCAAUGGGAAAUCCUUUGCUUUCGUUGGUCCCAGUCGGUACCUCCUUUUCCACCUGGUGAAGUACAUCUUUGCUGUGGCUCACAGAUUGUUCCUCCCAUUCCCCUUGCCGCUUUUUGCCUAUCGAUGGGUAGCAAGAGUCUUUGAAAUAAGCCCAUUUGAGCCCUGGAUAACAAGGGAUAAAGUGGAGCGGAUGCACAUCACAGACAUGAAAUUGCCUCACCUGCCUGGCUUAGAAGACCUUGGUAUUCAGGCAACACCACUGGAACUCAAGGCCAUUGAGGUGCUGCGGCGUCAUCGCACUUACCGCUGGCUGUCUGCUGAAAUUGAGGAUGUGAAGCCGGCCAAGACCGUCAACAUUUAGUGCCUCCUGAGCAGCUCUUGGUUUUGGCGUCUUUUGGGUCGGCCCAUGUGGUUUGAGCACCCAGCCAGGCGGUCUCUUUAGAGGAUCCUGUACACAGUUCCACUAUUAAAACAUUUCAGGUUGAAUUCUGCAGUAUUUUCUUCCUUGAUUUACAAAAUGAGAAAUGUAGUCACUUAGAACUUGAGCAUGAUUUUUGUUAAACAUAUUUAAUAAUGAUAUAUAUACUAUUUAUUCUCUGAAAUGCCAGAGAGUUUGAAUUUUCCUAUGACAAACCACUUCUAGCAUACGUUCUAGAAGACAAGGACCCUUUUUAAUGUCAAAGUAUUGUAAAGACCCCAAGUGAUAUGUGAUUGUUUUUUAAUUUCCAUUAAAUGAGAGAGCAUACAGUAUCCCCUAACCUGAAUGUGUUUACACUGAAGGUGUUUUUAAAAUUUAUUUUAAUAAUGUCCAUAUGCCUUUUAAAAAUAGUAGUACAUAUAUAGAAAAACAUUGUCCAUAGAUUCUCAAACCCCUUGCAGUAAUUCCACAGUCUUCUUGGAUCUGAGCUAUCUGAGGCCAGCCCGAUGCCCUUAGUACCACAUCUGGAUUAUUUCAGACACAUAGGUGGAGAUAGAUUCUCUUCACAUGCAAAGGAGAUGCUUCAGCUUCUAUGCCAGCAGUGCCAGCACUUAGGAAUUAUGACCUUCUAAUGAAGUUCUUAAAAUUGCAGCCAAGACCCAGAUGAACAUUUGGUUUAGUGUUGGCAAAUCCCACCAGUACAGUGUGAUUUAAAACUCCCACAAUUUGUGGUGAAGCCAACAUACCACCAUCCUAGGUGACCCAGGGUUGGUCAUUGUGUUUCACUGGACUUCAGCCUCCUGAUCUAUAUUUGGGACAGGGAUGUCAGUAAAAACGCUGUUUGAUGAGGGAAUGCCCGUCUCCUUACAGAGAGAAAGGUAUAUCAGUGUUGAAGGUAAGUUCUCCACCUGCCCUUUCUGCCUGCAUCAGAAUCUUUUUAUCCCAAAACGGUCAACAGUGAGCUACUCCAAGUGUGGUCCAUAGAUCACCAGCAUUGGGAUCAUCUUGGGGCUUGUUAGAAAUGCAGAACCCGGGCUGGGCACAGUGGCUCACACCUGUAAUCCCAACGCUUUUGAGUUGCUGUGGUGGGACGGUCGCUUGAGGCCAGGAGUUUGAGACCAGCCUAGGCAAUAUGGCAAGACCUUGUCUCUACAGAAAAAUUUCAAAAAGUUAGUAGGGCAUGGUGGCACGCACCUGUAGUCUCAGUUAUUCGGGAGGCUAAGGUAUGAUGAUUGCUUGAGCCUGGGAGUUCAAGGUUACAGUGAGCUAUGAUAGUGCCACUGCACUUCAGCUUGGACUGAAGAUCCUGUCUCAGAAAAAAAAAAAAAAAAAGGCAGAAUCCUAGGUUUUGUCCUGUCCCAGGCGUGUUGAAUCAGAAUCUGCAUUUUAGCAAGGUCUCCAGGAGAUUUGUAUGCACAUUACAGUAUGAGAAGCACUGCCAUACAGAAGAGCUGUAUCAGAGUUCAGUGUGAUCCCUGUUAUUAAUCCAGGUUGCUGACCCCACCCCAGACCUACUGAAUCAGAGUCUCAGGAAGGAGGGCCCAGGAAUUUUAGUUUUAUUAAACAUUCUAGUUUAUUCUCCUGUACACUAGUAUGUCAGAAUCAGCGUACUAGGGAAAGGAACACAAACCCAACUUCACGUUUUUUCUUCAGAUGCUGUCUGUUAUUUUGGAUGACACCCCUCCUGGCCAUAAGCCAGCCAUUAGGCACAGAGAUGGGUGGAUUUAAUUUGAAAAGGAACUAUAAUUCUAUAAUGCACAGUGUCCUCUCUUAGAAUAUCUACACUUUCUUUCCUUUUUUUGAUUCUUAAAAAAAAACUUAUUGAUACAUAAUAGAUGUAAAUAUUGUCAGGGUAUAUGUGGUAAUUUGAUAUAUUCAUAUAAUCAAUCAGUGUAAUUGGGAUAUCCAUCACCUUAAACAUUUACCUUUAUGCUAGUAACAUUCAAAUUACUCUCUUCUAGCUAUUUUGAAAUGUACAGUAGAUUAGUAUUAACUCUAGUUACCCUACUGAUCUAUUGAACACCAGGUCUUACUUCUUCUGUCUUAACUGUAAUUAUCUUCAUUUUCUAGCAAUGCUAUUUCUCAUCUCUAACUUGUAUCAUCUCAGGAUGCUGUAUAUUUCUUUUAUUUUUUAUUUUUUAUUUUUUUAUUUUUAUUGAUCAUUCUUGGGUGUUUCUCGCAGAGGGGGAUUUGGCAGGGUCAUAGGACAAUAGUGGAGGGAAGGUCAGCAGAUAAACAAGUGAACAAAGGUCUCUGGUUUUCCUAGGCAGAGGACCCUGCGGCCUUCCGCAGUGUUUGUGUCCCUGGGUACUUGAGAUUAGGGAGUGGUGAUGACUCUUAACGAGCAUGCUGCCUUCAAGCAUCUGUUUAACAAAGUACAUCUUGCACCGCCCUUAAUCCAUUUAACCCUGAGUGGACACAGCACAUGUUUCAGAGAGCACAGGGUUGGGGGUAAGAUCAUAGAUCAACAGCAUCCCAAGGCAGAAGAAUUUUUCUUAGUACAGAACAAAGUGAAGUCUCCCAUGUCUACUUCUUUCUACACAGACACAGCAACAAUGUGAUUUCUCUAUCUUUUCCCCACAUUUCCCCCUUUUCUAUUCCGCAAAACCACCAUCGUCAUCAUGGCCCGUUCUCAAUGAGCUGUUGGGUACACCUCCCAGACGUGGUGGUGGCCGGGCAGAGGGGCUCCUCACUUCCCAGUAGGGGCGGCCGGGCAGAAGCGCCCCCCACCUCCCGGACUGGUCGGCUGGCUGGGCGGAGGCGCCCCCCACACAAACACUGAAGCCGUAGCAUUGACUAAGGAAACAAUUUUACCAUCCUAAGCUAGUGGAUGUCACCCUCUCAGUGUAUGGAGGUUGCAUAUGACAAGUAACUGGGAGCUGGGCAUAAGAUCUAGGACACUCAUAUCCAGGGUGAUUCUCUUCAUAAGGAGGCAUGGGCUGAGUCUCCAUUUAUAGGGGCUGUCCCCAUAGAGACUUCAAGCCACACCUUUCUAGGGAUUCAGGUUGCACAUUACCUGAUUCUCACAGUUGAUUUGAGCCUGCAAGACUGUAAACCCAUCCCAUUAUCAUGUUUUCUUCCUCAUUUACCUACAUUUAUCAUUAAACCUUUGUGAUUCAGCAAAUCUGUUUACCUUCUGAUUCUACUUUAAAUUCCGUUCAUGUUCUUCCUUGGCCCUCCUGUGUAUUUCCCACAGCUUUGCUAGGCCUUAAGAUCAUCUCACAUUCUUCAUCCUAAUGACAAAAAUAAGUUCUAUGGGCUGGGCGCGGUGGCUCUUGCCUGUAAUCCCAGCACUUUGGGAGGCUGAUGGGGGUGGAUCAUGAGGUUAGGAGUUCAAGACCAGCCUGGCCAAUAUGGUGAAACCCCGUCUCUACUAAAAAAUACAAAAAAUCAGCCAGGCAUGGUGGGGCCCACCUGUAUAUAGUCCCAGCCCAGGAGGGAGACUGAGGCAGGAGAAUCACUGAAACCUGGGAGGCAGAGGUUGCAGUGAGCUGAGAUCACACCACUGCACUCCAGCCUGGGAGACAGAGGGAGACUCUGUCUAAAAUAAAUAAUAAUAAUAAUAAUAAUAAAGGUACAUGAUGGAAGCAUAUAUGGGAAUAUAUGCAAAGAUCUCUGAGAAGAUAAAGAAAGGUCUCUGGAAGGAUUAGCAAAAACUCCAUAGAAAACGGAUUUUUAAAGCUGCAUCUUGAUGUUAACCUGCUGAAAUGUGUGUGUUGGACCGGGGUGAGGAGGAAGCAGUCAUUCAUGCUGUGGAAGAGAACAGCAUGAGCAAUUGCAGUGGGGCAUGAAUGAGUGGGUGGUUAUGAGUGGGAGGCAGAGUCCGUGAGUUGGGAGGGGCACAAGCGAGUUUAACCUUUACCUUGGAGGUGAUGCAGAGCAGUUGAGUUCCAUACAGAUUUGGCUUCGAAUAUGAGUUCCACUACUUCUUAGUUGUGAGAUUGGACAAGUCACUUGACCUCUCUUUGUCAGCCUCAGUUUUCUUGUUUAUAAAAUGGGGGUGAUAGUAAUAACUACAUGAUGGGAUAGUGAUGAGGAAUUAAAUGAGAUCAUGCAUGUAAAAUGCUGAGCCCUGCACAUAAUAAGAACUAAGUAAAUGUGAGCCAUUAUCAUUUAAGUAGGGAAUAUCAUGCCCAUCUGAGUCCAUACAUUUGUUUCCUGACUUAAUAAAAUAGCUGCCGUUCCUGAGAAGGAGGGAUUCCUAUUUCCCAAAUGCUGGAAACAGGGACUUAUAGAAGGUAAAUUGCCCCAUUAGUAAGUAGCUGAAUUGGUUUUCCAACCUGGAUCUUUCUGGCUACAAAACUGAUGCCUUGUUCCAGAAAGGAUUUAAGGAUGCUCAGGAGGAAGACAUUCCCAGAGUUACACUCUAGAAGGUCUUGGAGUGAAUGGGAGGUAUAGUGGAAUGGAGGGCGUAUUUGAAGAAACCCUUCCUGUGAAGGAAAAUCCAAGAGAAUGAAGUAAGGAGAGACUUAAACUUGAAAAGAUUCUUGUGAGAGAAGGAAAGGGGCUAUUUACAAUAGAGAAGAGACUAGAAGAAAGUCUGAACUCACCUCCCUGGAAGCAGAGGGUGGUGGGGUUUUUGAGGGCUGUGUGAGAGUGUAGAAGUACUGAGAACAAGAAGCCAUGUGGAUCCUGUGAGGGCCAGGAUGGGGGGGGGGGUCAUGGGUCAUCUGUGUUUGCUGAUUGGCUUUAUCCAAAGGAAGAGUAAACAUCUCAUCCUUAUGACAGGAAGUAGUCCUGCAGCUUGGAGCAAGGUGCCCACCAAAGUUAGGCACAUCCCACAGCAAGUGGGAGAAAGGAGUGCUAUCUCCUUUUGAGGUUACAUUUCAGAGAAUGGUUCCCCUGGGUCCUUGAGAAAGACAGUCCUGGGUUGUAAAACUGGCAAGAGGCUGAGGGAAGAUGUAUGUCUCAAAGGGGAACUCAAAUAAUUUAUAAUUUUAAGUUUUCUGAUGCUCUAAGGGAAGUCAGGUGCCUAAUAUUGGUGAUGUGGUUUGGAUGUCCCCACCCAAAUCUCAUGUUGCAAUGUAAUCUCCAGUGUUGGAGUUGGGGCCUAGUGGGAGGCGAUUAGAUCAUGGAGUAGAUUUAUCAUGAAUGAUUUAGUACCAUUCUCUUGGUACAAUCCUCAAGAUAGUGAGUUCUUACAAGAUCUGGUCAUUUAAAAGUGUGAGGCAACUCUCCUCACCCCUUGUUCCUACUCCUACCAUGUGAGGUGCUUGCUCCCUUUUCACCUACUGCCAUGACUGGAAGCUUCCUGAAGCCUCCCCAGAAGCAGAUGCCUAUGUGACGCUUCCUGUACAGCCUGCAGAACCAUGAGCCAAUUAAACCUCUUUUCUUUAUACAUUACCUAGACUCAGAUAUUUCUUUAUAGCAAUACAAGAAUGGCCUAAUCGUGUUAGGAAGAAGCCUGUCUGAAGUGCAGUCAGGCUGAGGGGAGCAUGAAGGCCAUCUUGAUGGGGGAAAUCUUUUAGUACCCUAAUGCGAGCAGAUGAUGAUGUUGUUGGCAGAGAGGGAGGGUAUAACUUGUGGUGCCUAGCCCUAGAGGGAAUGGAAGGGCCAGAAUCCAGAGCAUAGGUGGGAUUGUGUGGGCUGACAAGUAAUAGUAUAUGAUAGCAUAGUAUAUGAUAGCAGUAGUAUACGAUAGCAUGUGUGUGAGUCCAUUUUGUAUUGCCAUAAAGGAGUACCUGAAGCUGGGUAAUUAAUAAAGAAAAGGGGUUUAUUUGGCUCACUGUUCUGUAGGCUGUACAAGCAUGGCACUAACAUCUGCUUGGCAUGAGCCACCACACCCGGCCAGAAUUUUAUUUUUAGUGACUAGGCUUUCCUUUAAAACCUCUGUACUAGGCCGGGUGCAGUGGCUCGCGCCUGUAAUCCCAGCACUUUGGGAGGCUGAGGUGGGAGGAUCACUUGAGCCCAGGAGUUUGAGACCAGCCUGGGCAACAGAGUGAAACCCCAUCUCUUUAAAAAAAUAAAGCACUUGAAGCAGAACUUUUUAUCUGUCAUAAUCACUGCUAUGUCCACAGCACCUAAAACAGUCCCAGACAUCUGUUGAAUAAAUGAAUGAAUGAGGUGGGAAGUCUUUCUUUACACUUAGAUGAAAACUCCAUCGGACCCCAAAUUGUUCUGGUCUUGUUCAGGUAAUAAUUUUAAUUCUAUAAUAAAAUCUCAAGUUAUAAUAGGCUCAAUUUGAUAAUUAGGAUGCCCAGUGUUGUGUAAUAAUUAAAGCGUUAAAUUUCCUCUCUGCCCCACAGCUGGGAUCCAAGAAGACCCUGUGGCUGGCUACUCUUCUGUAUUUUCAUUUAUCUCCACCCCCAGUUUACCAGCAGUGGUUAUCCUCUCUCCAAGACUGGGCCAGGGGUGAGAAGGGCAGUCUUACCAGGCAAGGGUCUUUGCUGACAGAUGUCUGGGCCUUCUUGACAGCAGGUGUUUAAAGCUGAAUCUGGUUCUACUUUCAGGAGAGUGAUGGUUUGAGAUGGUAACUGAAGUUGUAGAAGUAGAUGUUGAGGAUGAAGUAUCAUAUUAAUAAAACAUUGCCCAUUAACACCUUAGCACAAAUUAAAACUAGCUAUACCUCACUGAUAAGGACCUGAAUGGCUAAAUAAUGAUGAAUGAUUUAUGGAUGUAGCGGGGAACUGGGUGGAAGCAGUAGUAAGAAAUUUGAAUUAAGGAAUCGUAAGGGAAUCGAGAUUAUCUAGUUUCCCCUCGACAUUUUAUAACUGAAUAAACAAUAAAAAACAAGAGAAGUGACAGCUUUAUAGCAUCUGAUUGGGGAAAAACACAUCUUUUCUGGGGCUAGACAGUCCAUAAAUAGGACUUGGAAAUGGAAGUGUAGGGGGAGAUCCCAUUGUACUUCAGUGGAAAACUAUGCAUUGUCUGGAAUCUAGACUCUGGACAAAGACCCUUCCUUCCUGGCUGUUUGAUUUUGAUUCUAUGGGAGCUAUCUUGCAACUCUGUAAGCUGUAGGUAACUGAUAGCAGAGCAAAAUAAUUCUUGUCUAUAGACGUGUACAUUGUGUCUUAGCGUAGAUUCACCCGACCUCCUUCCCCAGUUUUGCUUCUAUUAGCACAUUUAUUUCAGUAAUUUUGAUCUUUGGAUUCUCCUUGGACAUUCCUCACUGAAAAAUGAAAUAAAAUUUUUGGCAUGUGCUCUUCUUUUGCA